AUCAUUUGCUUAGGUCUGAUCAAUCUGCUCCACACAAUUUCUCAGUGAUCCUCUGCAUCUCUGCCUACAAGGGCCUCCCUGACACCCAAGUUCAUAUUGCUCAGAAACAGUGAACUUGAGUUUUUCGUUUUACCUUGAUCUCUCUCUGACAAAGAAAUCCAGAUGAUGCGAGACCUGAUGAAGACAAUACAUGGAAAAUGACAGUCUUGGAAAUAACUUUGGCUGUCAUCCUGACUCUACUGGGACUUGCCAUCCUGGCUAUUUUGUUAACAAGAUGGGCACGACGUAAGCAAAGUGAAAUGCAUAUCUCCAGAUACAGUUCAGAACAAAGUGCUAGACUUCUGGACUAUGAGGAUGGUAGAGGAUCCCGACAUGCAUAUUCAACACAAAGUGACACUUCAUGUGAUAACCGAGAGAGAUCCAAAAGAGAUUACACACCAUCAACCAACUCUCUAGUGUCUAUGGCAUCUAAGUUCUCCCUGGGACAAACAGAACUCAUUCUUCUUUUGAUGUGUUUUAUUUUAGCACUGUCUCGAUCAAGUAUUGGUAGUAUAAAAUGUUUACAAACAACUGAAGAACUUCCUUCCAGAACUGCAGGAGCCAUGAUGCAAUUCACAGCCCCUAUUCCCGGAGCUACAGGACCUAUCAAGCUCUCUCAAAAAACCAUUGUGCAAACUCCAGGACCUAUUGUACAAUAUCCUGGACCCAAUGCUGGUCCACCUUCAGCACCCCGCGGUCCACCCAUGGCACCCAUAAUAAUUUCACAGAGAACCGCAAUA